AGUGCCUUUGGCGCACUGAGGUGCACAGGGUCCCUUAGCCGGGCGCAGGGCGCGCAGCCCAGGCUGAGAUCCGCGGCUUCCGUAGAAGUGAGCAUGGCUGGGCAGCGAGUGCUUCUUCUAGUGGGCUUCCUUCUCCCUGGGGUCCUGCUCUCAGAGGCUGCCAAAAUCCUGACAAUAUCUACAGUAGGUGGAAGCCAUUAUCUACUGAUGGACCGGGUUUCUCAGAUUCUUCAAGAUCACGGUCAUAAUGUCACCAUGCUUAACCACAAAAGAGGUCCUUUUAUGCCAGGUUUAAGCGAUUCUCCUGCCUCAGCCUCCCGGUACCCAAGAAUUUUAUACCUUCAGAAGUACUGCCAAUUUGGACUAAAAGAUUUUAAAAAGGAAGAAAAAUCAUAUCAAGUUAUCAGUUGGCUUGCACCUGAAGAUCAUCAAAGAGAAUUUAAAAAGAGUUUUGAUUUCUUUCUGGAAGAAACUUUAGGUGGCAGAGGAAAAUUUGAAAACUUAUUAAAUGUUCUAGAAUACUUGGCGUUGCAGUGCAGUCAUUUUUUAAAUAGAAAGGAUAUCAUGGAUUCCUUAAAGAAUGAGAACUUCGACAUGGUGAUAGUUGAAACUUUUGACUACUGUCCUUUCCUGAUUGCUGAGAAGCUUGGGAAGCCAUUUGUGGCCAUUCUUUCCACUUCAUUCGGCUCUUUGGAAUUUGGGCUACCAAUCCCCUUGUCUUAUGUUCCAGUAUUCCGUUCCUUGCUGACUGAUCACAUGGACUUCUGGGGCCGAGUGAAGAAUUUUCUGAUGUUCUUUAGUUUCUGCAGGAGGCAACAGCACAUGCAGUCUACAUUUGACAACACCAUCAAGGAACAUUUCACAGAAGGCUCUAGGCCAGUUUUGUCUCAUCUUCUACUGAAAGCAGAGUUGUGGUUCAUUAACUCUGACUUUGCCUUUGAUUUUGCUCGACCUCUGCUUCCCAACACUGUUUAUGUUGGAGGCUUGAUGGAAAAACCUAUUAAACCAGUACCACAAGACUUGGAGAACUUCAUUGCCAAGUUUGGGGACUCUGGUUUUGUCCUUGUGACCUUGGGCUCCAUGGUGAACACCUGUCAGAAUCCGGAAAUCUUCAAGGAGAUGAACAAUGCCUUUGCUCACCUACCCCAAGGGGUGAUAUGGAAGUGUCAGUGUUCUCAUUGGCCCAAAGAUGUCCACCUGGCUGCAAAUGUGAAAAUUGUGGACUGGCUUCCUCAGAGUGACCUCCUGGCUCACCCAAGCAUCCGUCUGUUUGUCACCCACGGCGGGCAGAAUAGCAUAAUGGAGGCCAUCCAGCAUGGUGUGCCCAUGGUGGGGAUCCCUCUCUUUGGAGACCAGCCUGAAAACAUGGUCCGAGUAGAAGCCAAAAAGUUUGGUGUUUCUAUUCAGUUAAAGAAGCUCAAGGCAGAGACAUUGGCUCUUAAGAUGAAACAAAUCAUGGAAGACAAGAGAUACAAGUCCGCGGCAGUGGCUGCCAGUGUCAUCCUGCGCUCCCACCCGCUCAGCCCCACACAGCGGCUGGUGGGCUGGAUUGACCACGUCCUCCAGACAGGGGGCGCGACGCACCUCAAGCCCUAUGUCUUUCAGCAGCCCUGGCAUGAGCAGUACCUGCUCGACGUUUUUGUGUUUCUGCUGGGGCUCACUCUGGGGACUCUAUGGCUUUGUGGGAAGCUGCUGGGCAUGGCUGUCUGGUGGCUGCGUGGGGCCAGAAAGGUGAAGGAGACAUAAGGCCAGGUGCAGCCUUGGCGGGGUCUGUUUGGUGGGCGAUGUCACCAUUUCUAGGGAGCUUCCCACUAGUUCUGGCAGCCCCAUUCUCUAGUCCUUCUAGUUAUCUCCUGUUUUCUUGAAGAACAGGAAAAAUGGCCAAAAAUCAUCCUUUCCACUUGCUAAUUUUGCUACAAAUUCAUCCUUACUAGCUCCUGCCUGCUAGCAGAAUUCUUUCCAGUCCUCUUGUCCUCCUUUGUUUGCCAUCAGCAAGGGCUAUGCUGUGAUUCUGUCUCUGAGUGACUUGGACCACUGACCCUCAGAUUUCCAGCCUUAAAAUCCACCUUCCUUCUCAUGCGCCUCUCCGAAUCACACCCUGACUCUUCCAGCCUCCAUGUCCAGACCUAGUCAGCCUCUCUCACUCCUGCCCCUACUAUCUAUCAUGGAAUAACAUCCAAGAAAGACACCUUGCAUAUUCUUUCAGUUUCUGUUUUGUUCUCCCACAUAUUCUCUUCAAUGCUCAGGAAGCCUGCCCUGUGCUUGAGAGUUCAGGGCCGGACACAGGCUCACAGGUCUCCACAUUGGGUCCCUGUCUCUGGUGCCCACAGUGAGCUCCUUCUUGGCUGAGCAGGCUUGGAGACUGUAGGUUUCCAGAUUUCCUGAAAAAUAAAAGUUUACAGCGUUAUCUCUCCCCAACCUCA